CUCUCCCCGGCCCGAUCCGCCCGCCGGCUCCCCCUCCCCCGAUCCCUCGGGUCCCGGGAUGGGGGGGCGGUGAGGCAGGCACAGCCCCCCGCCCCCAUGGCCGCCCGUCGGAGCCAGAGGCGGAGGGGGCGCCGGGGGGAGCCGGGCACCGCCCUGCUGGUCCCGCUCGCGCUGGGCCUGGGCCUGGCGCUGGCCUGCCUCGGCCUCCUGCUGGCCGUGGUCAGUUUGGGGAGCCGGGCAUCGCUGUCCGCCCAGGAGCCUGCCCAGGAGGAGCUGGUGGCAGAGGAGGACCAGGACCCGUCGGAACUGAAUCCCCAGACAGAAGAAAGCCAGGAUCCUGCGCCUUUCCUGAACCGACUAGUUCGGCCUCGCAGAAGUGCACCUAAAGGCCGGAAAACACGGGCUCGAAGAGCGAUCGCAGCCCAUUAUGAAGUUCAUCCACGACCUGGACAGGACGGAGCGCAGGCAGGUGUGGACGGGACAGUGAGUGGCUGGGAGGAAGCCAGAAUCAACAGCUCCAGCCCUCUGCGCUACAACCGCCAGAUCGGGGAGUUUAUAGUCACCCGGGCUGGGCUCUACUACCUGUACUGUCAGAGUUCCGAUGCCCUGGAAGCCUGGGAGAAUGGGGAGAGAUCCCGGAAAAGGAGAGCAGUGCUCACCCAAAAACAGAAGAAGCAGCACUCUGUCCUGCACCUGGUUCCCAUUAACGCCACCUCCAAGGAUGACUCCGAUGUGACAGAGGUGAUGUGGCAACCAGCUCUUAGGCGUGGGAGAGGCCUACAGGCCCAAGGAUAUGGUGUCCGAAUCCAGGAUGCUGGAGUUUAUCUGCUGUAUAGCCAGGUCCUGUUUCAAGACGUGACUUUCACCAUGGGUCAGGUGGUGUCUCGAGAAGGCCAAGGAAGGCAGGAGACUCUAUUCCGAUGUAUAAGAAGUAUGCCCUCCCACCCGGACCGGGCCUACAACAGCUGCUAUAGCGCAGGUGUCUUCCAUUUACACCAAGGGGAUAUUCUGAGUGUCAUAAUUCCCCGGGCAAGGGCGAAACUUAACCUCUCUCCACAUGGAACCUUCCUGGGGUUUGUGAAACUGUGAUUGUGUUAUAAAAAGUGGCUCCCAGCUUGGAAGACCAGGGUGGGUACAUACUGGAGACAGCCAAGAGCUGAGUAUAUAAAGGAGAGGGAAUGUGCAGGAACAGAGGCGUCUUCCUGGGUUUGGCUCCCCGUUCCUCACUUUUCCCUUUUCAUUCCCACCCCCUAGACUUUGAUUUUACGGAUAUCUUGCUUCUGUUCCCCAUGGAGCUCCGAAUUCUUGCGUGUGUGUAGAUGAGGGGCGGGGGACGGGCGCCAGGCAUUGUCCAGACCUGGUCGGGGCCCACUGGAAGCAUCCAGAACAGCACCACCAUCUAGCGGCCGCUCGAGGGAAGCACCCGCCGGUUGGCCGAAGUCCACGAAGCCGCCCUCUGCUAGGGAAAACCCCUGGUUCUCCAUGCCACACCUCUCUCCAGGUGCCCUCUGCCUCUUCACCCCACAAGAAGCCUUAUCCUACGUCCUUCUCUCCAUCUAUCGGACCCCAGUUUCCAUCACUAUCUCCAGAGAUGUAGCUAUUAUGCGCCCGUCUACAGGGGGUGCCCGACGAUGACGGUGCCUUCGCAGUCAAAUUACUCUUCGGGUCCCAAGGUUUGGCUUUCACGCGCUCCAUUGCCCCGGCGUGGCAGGCCAUUCCAAGCCCUUCCGGGCUGGAACUGGUGUCGGAGGAGCCUCGGGUGUAUCGUACGCCCUGGUGUUGGUGUUGCCUCACUCCUCUGAGCUCUUCUUUCUGAUCAAGCCCUGCUUAAAGUUAAAUAAAAUAGAAUGAAUGAUA